AUUCUGCUCAAAUAAAGCCUAGGCCAAACUGCACAAAUCAGAUUGACCCAGUCGACAGGAUCUGAACUUCCAGUGACCAUCCCAGGAACAGAAAGCAACUGUGUUACCAGUUCUGCUUUUCCUGGACCUGUUCCAAGCUCUCACGUUCCACAUCACACAUGGGACAUCUAGUGUCAGGCUCCCAGAGAGCAGGAACCAGGUGAAAUAUAAGAGCACAGUCCUCCCAGCCGGUGGCAUGGGGAUAAUCGGACAAUACAACUCUCCACCCUUUUUUAUGACUUUGGAAGUGAGAGCACUUCCUCAUAGACCUUGGAUGUGGGAGGAUUGCAUUCAGUCUAGUUCCUGGUUGCCGGCUGAAAUAACCUGACCGAGAGCAUCACCCCCUGAACAUGGACUUGCAGAAUUCCACAGAAGAGAGGAGACUGGCCUAGACAGACAGCCCCAGGAGCUGAGGGCCCAACAGGCUUUCUACCCUGGAUGCUGCUCCCAUGCCCUGACAUGAGGCCCACUACAAUGCUCUCCAAAAUGUCCACAAAAGUGACUUAAGUCAGGUUCCCCCAAACCAGACACCAAGACAAGAAUCCAUGUGUGUGUGACUGAAGGAAGUGCUGGGAGAGCCCCAGCUGCAGCCUGGAUGUGAACUGCAACUCCAAAGUGUGUCCAGACUCAAGGCAAGGGCACUAGGCUUUCCAGACCUCCUACUAAGUCAUUGAUCCAGCACUGCCCUGCCAGGACAUAAAUCCCUGGCACCUCUUGCUCUCUGCAAAGGAGGGCAAAGCAGCUUCAGGAGCCCUUGGGAGUCCUCCAAAGAGAGUCUAGGGUACAGGUCCGAAAGUAGAAGAACACAGAAGGCAGGCCAGGGGCACUGUGAGAUGGUAAAAGAGAUCUGAAGGGAUCCAGACGUGUACAGAAGGGCCAUGCUGUUAUUACUCUUACACAAGGAGGCAGCCCUCGAGCCACAGGGUCCAGCUGUUGGCUAUAAUAGCCUACCGGUCUCUGAUGAUCACCAUGUUUCUGGAAUUCAAGCCAGGAAGAAGCAGCAAUCUGUCUUCUGGAUUAAAACUGAAGAUCAACCUACUUUCAACUUACUAAGAAAGGGGAUCAUGGACAUUGAAGCAUAUCUUGAAAGAAUUGGCUAUAAGAAGUCUAGGAACAAAUUGGACUUGGAAACAUUAACUGACAUUCUUCAACACCAGAUCCGAGCUGUUCCCUUUGAGAACCUUAACAUCCAUUGUGGGGAUGCCAUGGACUUAGGCUUAGAGGCCAUUUUUGAUCAAGUUGUGAGAAGAAAUCGGGGUGGAUGGUGUCUCCAGGUCAAUCAUCUUCUGUACUGGGCUCUGACCACUAUUGGUUUUGAGACCACGAUGUUGGGAGGGUAUGUUUACAGCACUCCAGCCAAAAAAUACAGCACUGGCAUGAUUCACCUUCUCCUGCAGGUGACCAUUGAUGGCAGGAACUACAUUGUCGAUGCUGGGUUUGGACGCUCAUACCAGAUGUGGCAGCCUCUGGAGUUAAUUUCUGGGAAGGAUCAGCCUCAGGUGCCUUGUGUCUUCCGUUUGACGGAAGAGAAUGGAUUCUGGUAUCUAGACCAAAUCAGAAGGGAACAGUACAUUCCAAAUGAAGAAUUUCUUCAUUCUGAUCUCCUAGAAGACAGCAAAUACCGAAAAAUCUACUCCUUUACUCUUAAGCCUCGAACAAUUGAAGAUUUUGAGUCUAUGAAUACAUACCUGCAGACAUCUCCAUCAUCUGUGUUUACUAGUAAAUCAUUUUGUUCCUUGCAGACCCCAGAUGGGGUUCACUGUUUGGUGGGCUUCACCCUCACCCAUAGGAGAUUCAAUUAUAAGGACAAUACAGAUCUAAUAGAGUUCAAGACUCUGAGUGAGGAAGAAAUAGAAAAAGUGCUGAAAAAUAUAUUUAAUAUUUCCUUGCAGAGAAAGCUUGUGCCCAAACAUGGUGAUAGAUUUUUUACUAUUUAGAAUAAGGAGUAAAACAAUCUUGUCUAUUUGUCAUCCAGCUCACCAGUUAUCAACUGACGACCUAUCAUGUAUCUUCUGUACCCUUACCUUAUUUUGAAGAAAAUCCUAGACAUCAAAUCAUUUCACCUAUAAAAAUGUCAUCAUAUAUAAUUAAACAGCUUUUUAAAGAAACAUAACCACAAACCUUUUCAAAUAAUAAUAAUAAUAAUAAUAAAAAAUGUAUUUUAAAGAUGGCCUGUGGUUAUCUUGGAAAUUGGUGAUUUAUGCUAGAAAGCUUUUAAUGUUGGUUUAUUGUUGAAUUCCUAGAAAAGUUUUAUUGGUAGAUGAGUAAAUAAAAUAUUGUAAAAAAACUUAUUGUCUAUAAAGUAUAUUAAAACAUUGUUGGCUAAUAUAAUUUGAAAAAAAGUGGUUUUUUGGAAGACUUAGGAUAUUAUGGUGCUACAUAAUUUUUCCUCGAUGCUCUCUUCCUCUCAUCUUUCUUGUCUCUUAAAUUACUUUACUUCCUUGCACACUUUGCCAUACAAGAAUGAACAUGAGCUUUUCUUGUGUAGAUCUGAGUUGAAAUCCUGUGGACACUGGGCGAAUUACUUUUUAGAUCUGUAGCUCUGACUCCUCAGGCAUAAAAUGGGAAUAAUGCUUUUACAGUUUAGUGGCGGAACUAAACUCCCAAAAUUAUUUGUUAUAUGGAUCAAGUAAUAACGUCAGUAAUGUUUUUGGUACAAAGUCAUUAUUUAAUAAAAGUUAUUGUUCCAUCUUGCUUGCCCCCCCA